GGAAGUGGGGCUCGGGUCCCGCGGCGGGGCUGGAGGCAGCGAGCGCCGUCGUCUGCCCGGGCCCGCCCAUCGGGGUCCCCAACCCCAUCCGGACCCCGCCGCCCGAGCGCGCGGCCCCGGAAGCACCCGCCUCCCGGCAUGGUGCUCAAGGCCUUCUUCCCCACGUGCUGCGUCUCGACGGACAGCGGGCUGCUGGUGGGACGGUGGGUGCCGGAGCAGAGCAGCGCCGUGGUCCUGGCGGUCCUGCACUUUCCCUUCAUCCCCAUCCAGGUCAAGCAGCUCCUGGCCCAGGUGCGGCAGGCCAGCCAGGUGGGCGUGGCCGUGCUGGGCACCUGGUGCCACUGCCGGCAGGAGCCCGAGGAGAGCCUGGGCCGCUUCCUGGAGAGCCUGGGUGCUGUCUUCCCCCAUGAGCCCUGGCUGCGGCUGUGCCGGGAGAGAGGCGGCACGUUCUGGAGCUGCGAGGCCACCCACCGGCAAGCGCCCACUGCCCCCGGUGCCCCUGGUGAGGACCAGGUCAUGCUCAUCUUCUAUGACCAGCGCCAGGUGUUGCUGUCACAGCUACACCUGCCCACCGUCCUGCCCGACCGCCAGGCUGGAGCCACCACUGCCAGCACGGGGGGCCUGGCUGCCGUCUUCGACACGGUAGCACGCAGUGAGGUGCUCUUCCGCAGUGACCGCUUUGAUGAGGGCCCCGUGCGGCUGAGCCACUGGCAGUCGGAGGGCGUGGAGGCCAGCAUCCUCGCGGAGCUGGCCAGGCGAGCCUCGGGACCCAUUUGCCUGCUGUUGGCCAGCCUGCUGUCGCUGGUCUCAGCUGUCAGUGCCUGCCGAGUGUUCAAGCUCUGGCCCCUGUCCUUCCUCGGGAGCAAACUCUCCACGUGCGAACAGCUCCGGCACCGGCUGGAGCACCUCACGCUAAUCUUCAGUACACGGAAGGCGGAGAACCCUGCCCAGCUGAUGAGGAAGGCCAACACGGUGGCCUCUGUGCUGCUGGACGUGGCCCUGGGCCUCAUGCUGCUGUCCUGGCUCCACGGGAGAAGCCGCAUCGGGCAUCUGGCCGACGCCCUCGUUCCUGUGGCUGACCACGUGGCCGAGGAGCUCCAGCAUCUGCUGCAGUGGCUGAUGGGUGCUCCCGCCGGGCUCAAGAUGAACCGUGCACUGGACCAGGUGCUGGGCCGCUUCUUCCUCUACCACAUCCACCUGUGGAUCAGCUACAUCCACCUCAUGUCCCCCUUCGUGGAGCACAUCCUUUGGCACGUGGGCCUCUCGGCCUGCCUGGGCCUGACGGUGGCCCUGUCCCUCCUCUCGGACAUUAUCGCCCUCCUCACCUUCCACAUCUACUGCUUUUACGUCUAUGGAGCCAGGCUGUACUGCCUGAAGAUCCAUGGCCUGUCCUCACUGUGGCGUCUGUUCCGGGGGAAGAAGUGGAACGUUCUGCGCCAGCGCGUGGACUCCUGUUCCUAUGACCUGGACCAGCUGUUCAUCGGGACUCUGCUCUUCACCAUCCUGCUCUUCCUCCUGCCUACCACAGCCCUGUACUACCUGGUGUUCACCCUGCUCCGGCUCCUGGUGGUCGCCGUGCAGGGCCUGAUCCAUCUGCUCGUGGACCUCAUCAACUCCCUGCCGCUGUACUCACUGGGUCUUCGGCUCUGCCGGCCCUACAGGCUGGCGGCUGGCGUGAAGUUCCGUGUCCUCCGGCACGAGGCCGGCAGGCCCCUCCGCCUCCUGAUGCAGAUAAACCCACUGCCCUACAGCCGCGUGGUGCACACCUACCGCCUCCCCAGCUGUGGCUGCCACCCCAAGCACUCCUGGGGCGCCCUGUGCCGCAAGCUGUUCCUUGGGGAGCUCAUCUACCCCUGGAGGCAGAGAGGGGACAAGCAGGACUGAGGGAACUGCUGGCUCGCCUGGCACCACCACACGGCCACAGCCAGCCAUCUGCUCUGCCAGGGUGGCACCAGCUCAGCUGGCGCAUGUCCUGUGCUUUGUGGACGCUGCUGUGUGCUCCUGAACACGGCAGGCCCUGCUAUCACACCUUGGGCUUGGAGGUCAUUGGGAGUGAGCAGAUGUGGGGGUGGCCAGCCAGGCUGGCCGCACUCCAUCACUGGCACUGCCUGCCUUGGGACCCGCUUCCCACCUGCUGCGGUCACCAUGGUGGCGAGCACAGCAACCCCAGGUGUCCAGAGCACUGCCCCAUGCCCACCCUGUGUACCCAGGUCCAGAGGGUCCGUCCACCACAGCAGCCCCAGGUGGAGGGCUGGUCUCCCUGGGGGCUCCCCAGUGGCUCUGCCCUGGCUGUGGGGGUGGAGGGACCUUGCCAGGAUGAACCCCCCAGUCCCAGGCACCCUCUAGCUCCCUCAGCCGAACAGCACCCUGCAUCUGGGGGAUUGAAGCAGUCGCUGACCCCCGUCCCCAGCGGGCCCGGGCCCUCACUCCCUGAACCACACGGGGUUUAUUUGCGGAUGUUCCCUGGAGAGGUCGCUUUGUGAAGAAACCAUCAGCAGGCUGUGAGCAUCGCCAGGCUGCUGUGGGGGCGGGAGCAGCCUCAGUGUCAAGGGCCCGCCCACUGACCCAGCCGUACCUAUUCGUCCACGGUGCCCCGUAGCAGCAGGUCCUGCGGCCAAAUCUGUCUCCCUUCAUGGGCCUCCCAGGGAAGGAGGAAGCCCUGCUGUGCAGACACCUCUGUGGCCCCCCAGGAGUGUGAGUGGCCUGGGGAGGGGGCCGUGGCACUGAGGCCGAAAGUGCCUGCCAGACGGCACGGUCUGGGUGCGGGUGUUCCCUGUGAGCCCGAGUCCGCUUCAGGAGGGGAGCCUGCAGGUGCCGGCUGGUGAGGGGAUGACGCGCUGUGGGUGGGAGGAGGCAGCGCCCAUCUCAGCAGCACCAGGACUGCCUGGGACUCCCUGGCAACCCAGCACCGGGGAAGCCGUCAGCUGCUGUGACAAUAAAACCUGCCCCGUGUCUGGA